GUCAUCACGCAGGGCCGAGUCGGCGCGGCCACAUCCUUUAAAUAUGGUCUUUUUUGGGCGCGCGCGACAAUGUGAGGAGUGGGGUGGAGCGUGUGUGGUGUGUGGCUGCGGCCUGGGCAAGAGCCGCCGCGGACCAUGAGGUUCUCGCAGGUCACUUUAUCAGUCUGCCUGGGGUCACAGGAGAAGUACUGAACAUGAGAGAUCAAGCCUGAUUUGUAGUCCUGAUGAUGUCUCUGAGUAAGUUCUGGAGGGAUCCUGCCUCUUGGAGCCUUCGCAGCCAGGCAGCUGUGAACUGUGAGCUAGAGUGAAGCAGAAAUCUAGGAAGAUGAGCUCCAAGAUGGUCAUAAGUGAACCAGGACUGAAUUGGGAUAUUUCCCCCAAAAAUGGCCUUAAGACAUUUUUCUCUCGAGAAAAUUAUAAAGAUCAUUCCAUGGCUCCAAGUUUAAAAGAACUACGUGUUUUAUCCAACAGACGUAUAGGAGAAAAUUUGAAUGCCUCAGCAAGUUCUGUAGAAAAUGAGCCGGCAGUUAGUUCAGCAACUCAAGCAAAGGAAAAAGUUAAAACCACAAUUGGAAUGGUUCUUCUUCCAAAACCAAGAGUUCCUUAUCCUCGUUUCUCUCGUUUCUCACAGAGAGAGCAGAGGAGUUAUGUGGACUUGUUGGUUAAAUACGCAAAGAUUCCUGCAAAUUCCAAAGCUGUUGGAAUAAAUAAAAAUGACUACUUGCAGUACUUGGAUAUGAAAAAACAUGUGAACGAAGAAGUUACUGAGUUCCUAAAGUUUUUGCAGAAUUCUGCAAAGAAAUGUGCGCAGGAUUAUAAUAUGCUUUCUGAUGAUGCCCGUCUCUUCACAGAGAAAAUUUUAAGAGCUUGCAUUGAACAAGUGAAAAAGUAUUCAGAAUUCUAUACUCUCCACGAGGUCACCAGCUUAAUGGGAUUCUUCCCAUUCAGAGUAGAGAUGGGAUUAAAGUUAGAAAAAACUCUUCUCGCAUUGGGCAGUGUAAAAUAUGUGAAAACAGUAUUUCCCUCAAUGCCUAUAAAGUUGCAGCUGUCAAAGGACGAUAUAGCUACCAUUGAAACGUCAGAACAAACAGCUGAAGCUAUGCAUUAUGAUAUUAGUAAAGAUCCAAAUGCAGAGAAGCUUGUUUCCAGAUAUCACCCUCAGAUAGCUCUAACUAGUCAGUCAUUAUUUACCUUAUUAAAUAAUCAUGGACCAACGUACAAGGAACAGUGGGAAAUUCCAGUGUGUAUUCAAGUAAUACCUGUUGCAGGUUCAAAACCAGUUAAAGUAAUAUAUAUUAAUUCACCACUUCCCCAAAAGAAAAUGACUAUGAGAGAGAGAAAUCAAAUCUUUCAUGAAGUUCCAUUAAAAUUUAUGAUGUCCAAAAACACAUCUGUUCCAGUCUCUGCAGUCUUUAUGGACAAACCUGAAGAGUUUAUAUCUGAAAUGGACAUGUCCUGUGAAGUCAACGAGUGCCGAAAAAUUGAGAGUCUUGAAAACUUGUAUUUGGAUUUUGAUGAUGAUGUCACAGAACUUGAAACUUUUGGAGUAACCACCACCAAAGUAUCAAAAUCACCAAGUCCAGCAAGUACUUCCACAGUACCUAACAUGACAGAUGCUCCUACAGCCCCCAAAGCAGGAACUACAACUGUGGCACCAAGUGCACCAGACAUUUCUGCUAAUUCUAGAAGUUUAUCUCAGAUUCUGAUGGAACAAUUGCAAAAGGAGAAACAGCUGGUCACUGGUAUGGAUGGUGGCCCUGAGGAAUGCAAAAAUAAAGAUGAUCAGGGAUUUGAAUCAUGUGAAAAGGUAUCAAAUUCUGACAAGCCUUUGAUACAAGAUAGUGACUUGAAAACAUCUGAUGCCUUACAGUUAGAAAAUUCUCAGGAAAUUGAAACUUCUAAUAAAAAUGAUAUGACUAUAGAUAUAUUACAUGCUGAUGGUGAAAGACCUAAUGUUCUAGAAAACCUAGACAACUCAAAGGAAAAGACUGUUGGAUCAGAAGCAGCAAAAACUGAAGAUACAGUUCUCUGCAGCAGUGAUACAGAUGAGGAGUGUUUAAUCAUUGAUACAGAAUGUAAAAAUAAUAGUGAUGGAAAGACAGCUGUUGUGGGUUCUAACUUAAGUUCCAGACCAGCUAGUCCAAAUUCUUCCUCAGGACAGGCUUCUGUAGGAAACCAGACUAAUACUGCUUGUAGUCCUGAAGAGUCAUGUGUUUUAAAAAAACCUAUCAAACGAGUAUAUAAAAAAUUUGAUCCAGUUGGAGAGAUUUUAAAAAUGCAGGAUGAGCUCUUAAAGCCAAUUUCCAGAAAAGUACCAGAAUUGCCCUUAAUGAAUUUAGAAAAUUCUAAACAGCCUUCUGUUUCUGAGCAAUUGUCUGGUCCUUCAGACUCCUCUAGUUGGCCGAAAUCUGGAUGGCCUUCUGCAUUUCAGAAGCCAAAAGGACGAUUGCCAUAUGAACUUCAGGACUAUGUUGAAGAUACAUCGGAAUACCUAGCUCCUCAGGAAGGAAAUUUUGUUUAUAAGUUAUUUAGCCUGCAAGACCUGUUGUUACUCGUACGCUGCAGUGUCCAGAGGAUAGAGACAAGACCACGUUCUAAAAAACGGAAGAAAAUCAGAAGACAAUUUCCAGUUUAUGUACUACCAAAAGUAGAGUAUCAAGCUUGUUAUGGAGUUGAAGCUCUGACUGAAAGUGAACUUUGUCGCUUAUGGACUGAAAGUUUAUUGCAUUCCAACAGCUCAUUUUAUGUUGGGCAUAUCGAUGCAUUUACUUCAAAACUUUUUCUACUGGAAGAAAUUACCUCAGAAGAAUUAAAAGAAAAGCUUUCAGCACUCAAGAUUUCCAAUUUAUUUAACAUCCUCCAACACAUUCUAAAGAAACUAAGUAGCUUGCAGGAGGGUUCCUACUUGUUAUCUCAUGCAGCAGAAGAUUCUUCACUCCUGAUUUAUAAGGCCUCUGAUGGAAAAGUUACUAGGACAGCAUACAAUUUGUAUAAAACACAUUGCGGCCUUCCUGGUGUACCUUCCAGUCUCUCAGUUCCCUGGGUCCCAUUAGAUCCCAGCCUGUUAUUACCAUAUCAUAUCCAUCAUGGAAGAAUACCUUGUACUUUUCCACCGAAAUCACUGGAUACCACAACACAACAAAAGAUUGGUGGAACGAGAAUGCCUACACGCAGCCACAGGAAUCCAGUUUCCAUGGAAACCAAAAGCAGUUGCUUGCCUGCUCAGCAAGUUGAAACUGAAGGAGUGGCUCCACAUAAAAGAAAAAUAACUUGAGGACUGUACCAUGGAAAACUAAAUUUAAAAAAACAGUUAUAACAGUGUUUAAUUUAGAUAAGUUUGAGGGAAAAUAAUCAGUAGGCAAGAGGAACAUUUUUCCUGUAGUAGCUAGAGUGCCUUGAAAAAAUGUGUUGGCUAUGUGAAGGAAUAUUUCAACUAAAAUGGAAUGGUAUGCUUUUCACCCUUGAAGUUUGAGGAGGAUCUUGAUAUGUUUUAACAUUAUCAUGGCAGGGAAAUAUAUAAAGAAGAAAAAUAUUUUUACAUUAAACCUUUUCUAAAAAUUGUAAAUAGAAAAAUAAUUUGGUUUUUUAUCAAGAACAACACUUAUCGUUAUGUAUUGUGUUAGUUAUAUUGCCAGUCUGUUGCGACUGACUCAAAAAGUUAAAUGUUGCCACUGCUGAAGAUGAUUAUGAGCAUCGCAAACUUUGUUUCUGACCCAUUUUGACAGUUUUUAUAUACUCCUUUAAAAUGAUGAAUGUUACAGGUUAAUAAAGUUAAUACCUUUAAAAACUUGGUGAAAUUCCAUUACAGAAGCCAAAAAUAAAAACUCCCUGCCUCUGAAAAGUCAGAUUACUGACUUCUUGUUUGGCAACCAUCAGUUUGUUUAAUAAAAGAAAAAAUUUGGUGGUAUAACAUGUUUGAUGACAGAUGCCUCUAUCUCUAGAUUCAAGCUGAGUGUUGAAAUACACUGCUGAAAGCAAAGAGAUAGGUAUGUUUUCCAGAAAAAAAGUCAGUGUCAUUGCUCCAGAUGACAAGGUUAAUGUGGUAAAGCAUAAGCUUUUUUUUUUUUUUGAGAUGGAGUCUCGCUCUGUUGCCCAGGCUGGAGUGCAGUGGCAUGAUCUCAGCUCACCACAACAUCCACCUCCUGGAUUAAAGCGAUUCUCCUGCCUCAUCCUCCCGAGUAGCUGGGACUACAGGCACCUACCACCAGGCUUGGCUAAUUUUUUUUUGUAUUUUUAGUAGAGACAGGGUGUUACCAUGUUGGCCGGGCUGGUCUCAAACUCCUGACCUUGUGAUCCGCCUGCCUUGGCCUCCCAAAGUGCUGGGAUUACAGGGGUAAGCCACCGUGCCUGGCCAGCAUAAGCUAUUUUUAUCCUCAUCUAUACUGAUUGAUUUAAAUUUUCCGGGCCUGCAGAUGAAUUUGGAAAAGGGCAUAAUCAACUGAUGUUGCUGUAGCAAAUUUGGACUUAAGAAACUACAGACAGGGCCGGGCGUGGUGGCUCACACCUGUAAUUCCAGCACUUCGCAAGGCCGAGGCGGGAGAAUCACUUGAGUCCAGGGGUUGGAGACCAGUCUGGGCAACACAGACCUCAUCUCUACAAAUAAAAAAGUUAGCCGGGUGUGGUGGGGUGUGCCUGUAGUCCCAGCUACUCAAAAGGCUGAGGCAGAAGAAUUGCUUGAGCCCAAGAAGUCAAGGCUACAGUGAGUUGUGAUCGCACCACAGAACUCAGCUUGAGUAUCAGAGUGUGACCCUGUCUCAAAGAAAAAAAAAAACAGGACAGGCUUGUUUAAUCUUUAGAACCCUUACACUAAAAUUUUCAGAAAUUAUGUAUGUCAUUUGUAAAAUAUAAGUUUUGUAAUCCUAGAUAAUUGCUUCACAUUGAAAUUUUUUAGCUAUUCUGUGUAAAGAAUAGCUAUUCUUUUGGCCUAAUUUCUGAGAAAUUAGACCGAAAAAUCUCCUCAAGUAUUGUAACAGUUGAAAAUACUUAUAUUCAACUACCAAGUUUUGUUUCAUUUUGAUUUUUUGUUAUAAAACAUUUUUAAGUUAUUUGAGAAGUAAUUAUUAGUAAAAUUGUAUCUUGAUAAAUCAUUUCCUCAUCCUGCCAUUCCCUUUUAUAAAACACUGAGUUUUUUUAUUCCUUAAGUCACAUAUCCCAGAAAUGUUUUGGUUGUGAAUCAUUUGCCAGCGAGCCAAGGGAGAGGCAGGGAUUCCCUUGAAAUGUACUCUUACACUUUUUUAUUUUAUUUUUAAUGUACAUUUGUGUGCACCAGAAUGGAAUGUGCUCUUUUUAAAGAGCUGGACAGUGGUUGCUUCAGACUUCUGAAUACCAGAAAGACUUGCCUUUUAAUUUUUAAAUAUUACUUUUUACAUCAUAAAAUGUGUUAUCUUAUCCAUGUAUUUGAAUAACAUCAUAUAUAAAGGUAGUUUUUUGCUUGUGCUUAGUGAAGCCUCCUUUUUUAACAUACAUUUGAUAUGCUUUAUGUUCUUUUUCUUGAUUUUUAGUACUGAGAAUUUAUAAGCCAAGAAGUAACUGACAAUAUGUUUAGCAGGAUGUAAUCCCAGCUACUUGGGAAGCUGAGGUGGGAGGAUCGCUUGAGUCUAGGAGUUUGAGGCUGCAGUGAGCUAUGAUGGUGCCACUGCACUCCAUCCUGGGUGAGAGAUCAAGACCCUAUCUCAAAAAAUGAGCAAGUUUUUUUUUUUUUUUUAAAUCAGACUUAGGGCUAGCAAGGAUGUGAUCACCCUGGCCCAUUUAUACCUCAGCAGUGAAGGUGUAAUUUAUACACACCUCUUUGAAAACAGUUUAAUUCAGUAAGUGAGUGCAACUAUGUGCCAUGCACUCCAAAGUAGGUCCCCACAGUUAUUCUCUCAUAGCCUUGUUUUUUCAGAUCUCACCAUAUUUAUUUGUUUCUUUGAUUUUCUUUUCUUAUAGAUUACAAGCUCUGCAAGGACAGGGGCAUAUUUGUUUUGUUCACCAUUAAGUAAUAAACACCUAAUACAGUGCCUGUCAUGUAGUUGCUUAGCAGAUAUUAGUUAGAUGCAUGAAUGUGUAGGUAUCAAAGAUUUUUUUUUUCAGGAGAUCACAUUCUAGUGGAAGACACUAUACUGCUUUAUGUGAUAAGUGCUUUGAUAAAGUAAGCAAGUCAUCUAACCAGAUCUUGGUAGUUAAGGUUUUCUGAGAUAGAACUUGAGCUGAGUCUUUUAAAAAUAGUAGGAUUUAUAAGGGAAAAUUAAAGGUCUUCCACAAAGAAACUAAGUGAAACUAAGCAGCCUAUGAAAAGGUGAAAGUUGGAGAGAUUAUAGGCUAUGAACAUGGGAGAUGAGAGAGAAAACUGCAGGAUAGGGACAGAAACACUGUGCUAAGACAUUUGAACUUUGUCCUGUGCAAUGUGGGAACCAGUAGUGAAGGUUAAUUAACUGACAUGAUCAGAUAUGUAUUUGAAAAGGGCUCUUGUUGGCAUUAGUCUAGAGAAUGCGAUGGAGCUGGGAAGCGAAAGAAGAAAUGUUGGGAGCCUGUGUUGUAGUAACUGAAAAAUGGCAAUGGCCCAGAAUUAAAGCAGCAAGAAUAGGAGUGGGCUCAAGUGAUGUAUAAGGAAAAAAAAAAAAAUGACAACUCAGUUUUGUUGUUGGUAAGGAGAGUAAAGUAUGGCUUCUGGGUUUCUCAUUUGAGAUACUGAGUAAAUGAUGGUGUUAACCCAUUGAGAAAAUAGUGUGGUUAGAGUGGGAAGAAAGUUAAUUUAAAAUGUUCAUUUUUUUUUUUAGUCAUUUCUACUUUUGGAUUCUAGGUUUGUGUGCUAUAUUGGUUAUAACCAAUUUGCUGAAUAAUAAAUUAUCCCAAAACUUAGCUACUUAAAACAACAAACAUUAUCUCACAGUUUCUGUAAGUCAAAAGUCCAGGUCUCUCAUGAAGUUGCAGUCAGGCUCUUGGCUAGGGCUGCAGUCAUCUGAAGGAUUAGUAAGUCGCUAAGCCCACACUUAAGCUCCACCCUUGAAGGGAGAAGUUUGGAAAGAAUUUGUGAACAUAUUUUUAAAUCACAUAUGCUAUGAACAGGUUUAGGGGAGGGAGAGGAAAGAAAACUUUAACUUUUCAUUAGCAUACUGCAUCUGUAGUUCCUAAUGGGCAUGUUGUAAAGAUGUUAAGACGUUUUCUAUGCAUUAUAGGUAUAUAGUAGUAUUUUGUUUUGUUCUGUUUUUUUGUUUGGUAUGUAGUAGUUUUUAAUCAAACCUUAACGUAUUUGAUAUUAAGAUUUAUUGAGUUUCUUGUUGAGAUGUAGAAAUAAAGGGGAUCCAUUUCAUUUAUCCA